ACUCUCGCCCGGACGGCCGCGCGGACACACGCUCUGUACACACGCGCGCGGCGGCGCGGGGCCCCGAGACACGCCCGCCCCCACCCCGCCGCCCCCACCCCGGCGCCCGCCCUCCGCGCCUGGCCCCGGCCCGCCCUCGGCCUCCCCCGCCCCUCCCCGUCGCCCGCCGAGCCCGGUCAGCCGCCGCGAGCAUGCACCCGACGAGCUAGGAGGAAGCCCGGAGCCCCGCAGGAAGCGCCGAGGCCGGCCCAGCCCGCCGCACGCGCCGCCCCCCGCGGGCAGCGCCCCCUCCCCUGCGGGCGCCCCCAGCCCCACACCCCCCCACCUUCCCGGGGGGUGGGGGGGUGCGGGCCGCCGGAUCCGGGGGCCCCGCCGCCCCAGCAGCCCAGGACAGCCCCCUCUCCCCGCCCCCAGCCCCCUCCCCCGGCGCGGCCAUGGAUGUGACCAGCAGCUCGGGCGGCGGCGGCGACCCCCGGCAGAUCGAGGAGACCAAGCCGCUGCUGGGGGGCGACGUGUCGGCCCCCGAAGGCACGAAGAUGGGCGCCGUGCCCUGCCGCCGGGCUCUUCUGCUUUGCAACGGGAUGAGGUACAAACUGCUGCAGGAGGGCGACAUUCAGGUCUGUGUCAUCCGGCACCCGCGGACCUUUCUCAGCAAGAUCCUCACCUCGAAAUUCCUGAGGCGCUGGGAGCCGCACCACCUAACGCUGGCCGACAACAGCCUGGCGUCCGCCACGGUGUGGACGUUGAGGGCCAGCCUGGAAGCGCCAUAUCCAGAGGCACUCAGGGAGGGGAGCAGGAGACCCAGGGCUCUGGGAUUCAGGUCCCUCUGUCACACCCUGCCCUUCUUCUGGGUCUUUCUUCCCCACCUCCCAGCCAGAAAUUGCCUCCUGGAGCCAGCCCAGCCUCGUCUUGUUCAUUGGAGCUCAGUUGGAGACCCGUCCUCACCCGAAGCAGGGUGAGAGGACAGCACCUGCCACCUUUAAGUCUGGGCUUUGCUGGACGCCUAGGAGAAGCCGGGUCCUCAGGCACUCGAGUGGGAAGUGAAAGUGUGCACCAGCUCUUUAGUUCUGCUAUUGACCGGACAGGGUUUUUCCUGGGGGGAGGGGGAAGGAGCUGCUGUGUUUUCUUUGCUUAAUCUGGCCUUGCCCCACAGAGAAAACACAUGCGUAGCCUCCAUCCUGUUUGUAAAGAGGGCGGUCAGCUACUCGAAGUUGCUCGCCUGGAAAAACUGGGAAGAUGUCAUCUCCUAUGGUAAGGAGGUGGGGGCUACAGGUAGCUGAGGUGGGCAAUGAAUGUCUUGAGGGACUGUCAGCAUGUGACCUUUUUUUAAAUGGUGAUAAAAUACACGUAACAUAAAAUGGGCCAUUUUAACCAGUUUUAAGUGUGCAGUUCAUUGAGUACGUUCACAUUGUUGCACAACCAUCACCCCCAUCCAUCUCCAGAACUUUCUCAUCUUCUCAAACUGAAACUGUCCCCAUUAAAUGUUAACUCCUAGUCCCCCUCCCCCAGCCCCUGGCAGCCACCAUUCUCUCUUCAUUUUCUAUGACUUUGACUCCUUUAGGGACCACAUAUGAAUGGGUUAAUAUAGGAUUUGUCUUUUUCGUGUCUGGGUUAUGAUUAUUAUUAUUUUGCUUUUUUUGUUGAGGUGAGAUUUACAUAACAUAAAAUCAACCAUUUUAAAGUGAAGAAUUCAGUGAUAUUUAGCCACUACCACCUCUGUCUAGUUCCAAAACAUCGUCACCCCAGAAGGAAAUCCUGUACCCGUUAACAGUCACUCCUCUUUCCCCCUACCCCCGGCUCUUGAAAACCAACAUAUGACUUUAAAUUUGAUUUGCAUUUGCAUAUAUUAGGCCCUCUACAAAUGUAUGCUGAAUGAAUGAAAGAAAAUCCUGGCCAGCUGAGAAAUAAUGAUGAAAGCUUGGAUUUCUUGAGUGCCUACUUUGUGCCAGGUCCACAUAAGCAUGUGUGGUUCUCAGCCCUGGCCGCACAAUGGGAUCACCUGGGGAUCUUCGUAACCCCCAAAACCCAGGCCCCACCCCAGAGACGCUGAUGGCUUUGGUCUGGGGGAGGUCUGGGCCAUAGCCUUUUCCGAGCGAUUCUAACAUGAGAGUGAGUGGUAGGCAGUAUUUCCUUGGGUCAUAGCAGUCCUUUGGGGUAGGUAAUAUUAUCUCCAUUUUGUGGAUAGGGAAACAGGUUAUAGAGGUCAGGUAACUUACCCAAGCUCUCUCAGCUUCAAAUCUCCAUCUGAGGCCAGGCGUGGUGGCUCACGCCUGUAAUCCCAGCACUUUGGGAGGCCGAGGUGGGCAGAUCACCUGAGGUCAGGAGUUUGAGACCAGCCUGGCUAGCGUGGUGAAACCCCAUCUCUACUAAAAAUAUAAAAAUUAGCCAGGCGUGGUGACACACACCUGUAAUCCUAGCUACUCAGGAGGCUGAGGCAUGAGAAUCGCUUGAACCCGAGAGGCAGAGGCUGCAGUGAGCCAAGAUCGUGCCACUGCACUUCAGCCUGGGCGACAGAGUGAGACUGUAUCAAAAAAUAAUAAUAAAAUCUCCACCUGAGUCCAAAGCCCUGACCCAUUCUGCUGCUCCAGCCUCCCUCUGUUGUUUUGCAGGUGAUUUUGGAAGGGGCACCUGUUGCUACUUAUGUGUUUGCUAUGGGGUAAAAUAAUUAAAAACUAUCUAAUUGGGAUUUAUGGGGUGCCAGCUGUAUGCCAGGCACUGAUUCACGUUCUCUCAUUUUACCUUUACAGCCACCUUGUGCAAGGGGACUGUUAUGAUGACAUCAGUUUCCCCAACAUUGUUGGGAAAGGACGGGGGUGGUUUGCCUCACUUAUCAUGGAGGGAGUCUCCCCUUGGCCCUCCUGGUGGGGACCUCAGCUGAAGCAGAGUGGGAAAGAAGCCUGUGUGUGAUGUCAGGGUGGGGUCCAAAGUUGAGGCUGAAUGCAGUGUUUUCACGGGAUGGCUUUGACAUCGGUGAGAGCUGCUCUGCCCAGUUUGAACUAGUGGUGGGCCAUUGAAUGGAGCUGGAGAAGCUGUGCACACCUCAGGGCUUUGGCCCGGCUGUCUCCCUCAGCUGCACAUGGUUUGUCCCUCCUAUUUGCGUUUGAGAUUUUUGAUGGCUGUGGGACUCAUGAUUUAUUCAACAAAUAUUGUUGAGACCUGAUAGCUGGGCGCCGUCUGGGGCUCUUAGGAAUAUGCGGUGAUGAGACAGGCACAGUCUCCAUUAUCCUCAUGGUCUGGCAGGUGGUACGGAUUGUUGUGUCACCCUCAUCUGGGUGUGCCGGGCCCUGUCUCUGCAUGAGCUCCCUCAUUCCAGCCUCAUGGCAGGUGUACAGGUGAGGGCCUUGAGCGACUGUGUGUAACAGAUGAGGACAGGGCCGCUCAGGAAGGCUGAGAAGCUUUCCCAACGUUACACAGCUUGUGAGAAGCGGAGACUGAAAUUGAAUGUGAGCUGAUGGCUUCAGAGCUUGACUAAGUAACACUGACAGAUAAUUAUGAAAGAGGAAGUCCAGGGAGCAUCUGCGUGGGAUGGGGCCAUGCCAGGGCCAGAGCGGCUCCCAGAGGGUGCUGUUUCAACUGAGGUCUUGGGGGGAUGGGUACACUAGUUUCCUGUGGCUGCUAUGACAAAUGACCACAGGCUUUGUGGCUUAAAGCAACACAAAGUUAUUAUCUUACAGUUCUGGAGGUCAGAAGUCCACAGUGAGUCUCGUAGGGGCUAAAGUUGAGGUGUUGUCUUUCUGGAAGCCUAAGGGAAGGGUCUGUUGCCUUUUCCAUUAUCUAGAGGCUGCUCGCAUUCCUUCCCUCGUGGCAGCAUCACUCCAACCUCUGCUUCAGUCUUCACAUCUCCUCUGGCUCUGGCCCUCCCGCCUCCCUCUUUUUUUUUUUUUUUUGAGAGGGGGUCUCACUCUGUCACCCAGGCUGGAGUGCAGUGGCGCAAUCUUGGCUCACUGCAACCUCUGCCUCCCGGGUUCAGGUGAUUCUUGUGCCUCAGCCUCCUGAGUAGCUGGGAUUAUAGGUGUGCGCCACCACACCUAGCUAAUUUUUGUAUUUUUAGCAGAGACAGCGUUUCACCAUGUUGGCCAGGGUGGUUUCGAACUACUGACCGCAAGUGAUCCACCCUCCUUGGCCUCCCAAAGUGCUGGGAUUAUAGGCAUGAGCUACCGGGCCUGUCCCUGCCGCCUCUUAUAAGGACCCUGUGGUUACACUGGGCUCACCAGAUCAUUCAGGGGCACCUUCCGUCUCAAGAUCCUCAGCUUAAGCAACUCUAAGGGUCCCUUUGCCAUGUCAGGCCACAUAGUCACAGGUUGAAGGGAGUAGGAUGAUUAGGGCCAUUAUUGUGCCUAUCAUAGCAGGGGAGAGUGAGGCUGGUGGGCAGGCAAUCUAAGGCCUGGAGGUGAGUGGGUGCUUGGCUUUGGAGGGGUGCUGGGCGCCUAAGUACCUGGAGGAGGAGCUCCUGGAGGGGAGGGUGAGACAGCAGAGGGCCUUUUAAGUCAUGGGGCAGACUGGGAGUUGGUCACCUGCUAAGUAGCUUCUGGAGAGAGGACCUCUGUUCCCACUUGAGCCUGGUGGACAUGCGUGUCCCAGGAGGACGGUGUGUGUUGGGGAAGCCCCUGCCCCUCCCCCACCUAGGAGCUUCCCUUUCACAGUGACAGGAAGAGGGAGAGCUAGGAGCAUAAUGUGCUUUGGGCAGGAAAUGCAGGCUGCAUCUUCCCAUUGCUGGAGAAGGUGACAAACCCGGGCUUCGGAGUCACUGGGGCUGGGUUUGAAUCCAAACUCCACCACAUCCUAAGCUGAGCCCGUUCCCAACUGUAAAAUGGGGGUGAGAUAGGGCCUGACUCACAGGGUCAGCCCUGGGGUCAGCGAGGCAGGUCAUGGGACGCUGUUGGUGCACAGGCAUGCCUGCUUGCUCGUCCGUUCAGCAGAUGGCGGUGGCGCGUCCACUGUGCACCAGGCACCAUUGCAGGCACGGAGCAAAGCAGGCAUCAUCCUGGCCUACUUGGAGCCCCCAUUCUACUGGAGGAGAGGAAAAUGAACACGGAAAUAUAGAAUCUUGUCUGCUGCCACUAAGUGCUGUGGAGGAAACCAUCAGACGAGGGAGGACAGAAGUAUUGGUAUGAAUGGGGAGGGUGUGGCGUCUGUGUGUGGUGGCCUUUGGAAUAGGGUGACCAAAGAAAAUCUGGAUGAGAGGUGACACUUGAGCAGGUUUGGAAAAGGUAAGGGAGGAAGCUGUGCAUGUGCAAAGGCCAUGGGGCAGCGGCUAAAGGAGGUAAAGGAGCCAUCCACAGCAUGUGCAAAGGCCCUGGGGCAGCAAUUUACCUGGUUUUUUUUCUAGGAAUGCAAGGAGGUAAAUGUGGAUGGAGCAGAAUGUGCCUUGAGGAGGGUGGCAGGAGGUGAGCUCUGUGAGUCACUAGUGGGGUCAGAUGGUGUAGGGCCUUGUAAGAACUUUGGCCGUUAACUCUGAGGGAGAGGAGAGAGCUGUGUCUGCUCUAAUACAUUCAGGAAAGUGGCAGCUCUGAAGACCGAAGUGCCUCCUGGCUUGCCUCUCUCCCUCCCGCAGCCUCUUCCUCUUCCUCUUCCUCUUCCUCUUCCUCUUCCUCUCCCUCUCCCUGACCCUCCCCCAGCUGCCCACUGUUUUGUGGGGAUUGAUUGGGCCCAUUGAGGCCUGCUGCCUGGAGUAGCAGCCUUGCCCACAGUCCAGUCUGGGGACCUUUCUCGGCCAUCCCCUCCUCCAGCUAUCCUCAGUGUUGGUCACUUAUGGCUUUUGCUAUUUAUAUAGCACAGUGGUUUAUAAACUCUGCUUCUAGAAUUUCGCAACCCGUCCUGCAGCAUGUUAUCUGUCCAGGCAGAUAGUGGCGAUCUUUAUCCAAAUCAAAGGACUGAAAUUAAGGGGAUGGAAUUGUCUGCAUUUUAUGUUUUCCACCCAACAUAUUUUGUCAUAAACUGGGAACUUGUGUAAGGUGGCAUCCAGUUUAGUUCAAUCCUGUAUGUAAUCAUUUCAAGCUUAAUAAAUUAGUUAAUAUUUGUUAAACACCUACUGUGUCUUGGGGUUUCUGCGAGAUGUGAGAUUCAUUGGCGGACAAACCAGAUAGCGUUUUUGCCAAGUCACCGAGAUAGUUUCAGGUCCUUGGCCAUCAUCUUUUUCCACCAACUCCAGGUCAGCUCAGGGGCCCACCAGGUGGAAGUCGCCCUUCCCUGGCGGACCUCGCCCGUUCCCAUUCCUUCUGGCAAAGUCAGAUUUGGUGAAAAGGCCACAGCAGCUGGGUGGAGUUCCACUUGCCAGCUCGAGGAAGAGUUCUGGGAGGCACGGGAAGCCAAAACCGCCUGUGAAGGAGGCCUGGUGCAGCUCAGAAAGCCCUGGCUCUGGCCGAGGUUUGGGAUGUGUGGCUGCCAUGGCAACCCGUCUCCCCGACGAAGGGUAGACGGGUUGGGCGCCGAACGCAGGGUGUUGCAGGUUGGGCUCCAUUUUGACUCUGGUGGAGAACGAUCACCUGGCUGCAAAACCAACCUCCCCGCCCAGUACAAGCAUCUCCUCUUCCCCCUUGGGCCACGAGGGUGGGGGACUUGAGGCAGGAGUGGGUUUUUGUAGUGGGGUCAUUGGGUAAUCAUCUCCGGCUCUCUGCUGCAGUUGGUGCGCACAGACCCGGCUAGUUUAAGGCCAUUGAUGGGACUCCUGUAGACGCUAAGCGAUGGAAACAUUGUGCGCAUCCAGUACUCGGCGUGCUCUGGAUGGGGCUGGAAGAUGCCAGGUGGGCUUCUGAAACGAGUGUGGGGUUCACUCUACCUUUGAUCUUUGCCUGCCCGGGUGUCCUCAUUCAUUUAACUCUUGGCUUCCUUAUUCCUCUGUCCUUAUCCCCUUCCUAGGAGUGGGGUCUGCUCAGAUAUACCCUCUUCCCUGCCUCUUUCCCUCCCUCCCCUCCUGCCUUCCUCCUCCUACCCCUGAAAACCUCUUUUUUUUUCUGUCCAAGGCUUUCUUGGGCGAGUUUAGAGCAGCAGUUUCCAACUUGAGCUGCGCAUUGGAAUUACUUGAGGAGCUUAAAAAAUGUCCUGAUGCCUGACUCCACCCCCAGAGGUUGAGAUUCAUUUGCUGUGUAUGGGGCUCAGACGUCUUAUUUUUUAUUCCGACAUCAUUUGCUUGAAUAGCUGUGGAGUAUUCUAUUGCGUAUGUAUACCAGAAUGUAUUAAGCUACUUUCCUGUUGAUGGACAUUUAAGUUGUUCCUAAAUUUUCCUAGUAUAAUAUGUUCUCCAUCCAUCUCCUUGUGAGCUCAUAUCUGUCAAGAAAUACUGCGAACGACUUUGAAAUGGGUGGAGAAAGAUUCCUGGGUGUGUUGUCUAGCUCACUCAUCCGAGCUAUUUCUACCUUUUGUUUUCUUUGAGCUAUUUUACAACUCUAAUUGUGGAAAGCUGAUAAUACUGCAAGUGGUUCUGGUUCAUGAAAAUGCAAACCAGCUGUGCCUGUGGACUGCUGGACGUCCCAGCUUGUAGACACUCCCCAGGUGAUUCUACAGUGUGGCCUGGGUGGAGAAUUCCCAUUCGGAAGACUGGAGGUAAUUUCUUACCACAGCCCUUCUGAUGUCCCUCCCGACUCAGUGGGAACUGAUGGCCUAUUUAUUUAGCUGUAUGUUUACGCAGCCCGUGGAAAUAACAGUAAGAGCUAACAUUAACUGAGCACUUAUAAUAUGCCAGAUCCUUUUUUGAGAAUUUUAGGUGUUAUUUAGUUAUGUGAGUACAAUUUUUCAUAGACAGGGAACAACCUGGUGAAAUAGGUAGUCUUAUUCCCAAAUGCAGAAGGGGAAGCUGAGGCGAAAGAGCUUGCUGGAGGUGGUAUUGCUAAUGAAUGAUAGAGCUGGGGUGGCACCACGUGGCCUGCUUGGACCACCAUACUGUAGAGGUGGGAGUACCCAGCUCUCCCCUGGAUUCUGCCACUUCCCCGAAUGAGUCACUCAGGCGCUGUGAGUGUGUCAUGGGACCGAUGAUCCUAAGCUCCCAGACCUACUGCGGAGGGUUGAGGGGUUGGGCGUGAGAGCCUGGCACCCGGCCUGACAGGCAGAGAGGGGCUCCCAAAGGCCACACGCAAGGCCAUCACUCUGUUCUUGGCGUGUUGGUUUGCACGUUCAUUGCCUGCUGGCCAGAGCGAGCUGGUGUGUCAGACUCACAUGAACGGGCUUAGGGGAAGAAAGGGAGGCUUUUCCAUCACAGCCAGGCUUUCUCAGAGAUAUUCAGGUUCCCAAGAAGUGGCUGUGAGAUCUGGAGUUGAUGGACUUAAUUCAGAGACAAACAUGCGCACUCUGUGUUCAGGGCCUUGCAUCUGUUUCGUCCAUCCACUAGGCCUCAGAGCAGCCCUGGGAGGUAGAUAUGAUCGCGCCCAUUUGACAGAUGUGGAAACCAAGGAUCAUCCAUUUGUUCUUGGGUUUCUUUUCUAAUUCACCUCAUACGUCCUAGGCCCUGAGACGCAGUGGCAACUAGGAAAUUGCACUUCGGGUCCUCGCUGGAGUUCAUUCAGGAGGGGUGCCCAGGGCCGGGCCACUUUGCACUUGAGUGCACACAGUGACUCUCCAAGCAGACCGCCGAGUCCCUCCAGUCCCGCAGAGUUUCCGGGUGUCCUCAGCCACAGGAGGUGAGGCUGGAGUGGGCCGGCCCAUUGCCCGGUCCCCAGAGAGAGCCAGACUCCCCAGGAACUAAUUUCUUAAGAGACCUUGAAGGCUCUUAACUCCCUAAGCGAAUCCAGCUGUGCCUGGUGGCCGGCACUGUUGCAGAUGUCCUGGCCAAAGCCAGCUUGGUUUGGAAGCCCGGCCCCAACAGCCGCCAAGUCUGGAAAUGAAGUAAAUGAGUGAGUUGUUCUUGGCCAUUUUCCCCUCAUCUCAACCCAGCUCAAAUCAAACUGGAGCUCUGACCUCAGGCAUCGCACAUUCCAUACUCCCCGGCCUCCUGGGGUUCAAAGGCGCACGGCAGGCGAUAACCGCACUGGGCGUUGAGCGCCGUGAGGGAAGCUUCUGGAGGGAGCGUGGGACUGGGGUGGGGGCAGCUGGCGCAGCUUCGUUUCUCUGGACACCAGGCCUCGGAGAAACAGAAGGGGACGCCUGCUGGGCUGUGCUUGGCCUCUGGUCAUGGGGGGCCCUGAGAACCAGAACAGGCCCUGCAGGGGUGAGGCUUCUAGUGAACCGGGGGGGGUGUGGGGGCUACUUUGGGGUGCCCCCUCCCCACCCUCCCUUGCCUCCUGAGCCUCACUGCUCUACCUGGGAGCCCCAGCGUGACUUCUUGAGAAAUGGUGGCCUCUGCUAAGCAAGGCUGUCCCGGGCGGUCACGGCGAGCUGGCACCUGGAUUCCUGAGGUCCUGAGGAACCCGCUUCAAACCUGGGUGGUCAGGGCCGAGUGGGGCUCUGACUGCUCCACUCCCGAGGCCCCAGACCAAACCACACAGCCCUUGAGGGUGAAUCACUUUGAAGUGAGGGGUUCUGAGCCUGUGGCCUGCCAAGCGGGCCGGCUUGGCGGGAAUGGGCAGGCUGGGCAGCAUGGCCCGCGUGGCUUCCAGGCAGCAACUCCUCUCCCAAGGCGAAGGAAGCCAGAGCCAGAGCGCAAGGCUCUGGGCUUUGUGGUCAGAGAGCGGCUGAGUUCAGAUAUCAUUUCCUAGCUCUGUGACACUGGGCAAGUCACUUAACCACUCUGAGCCUCAGCUUGCUUUAUGUGCAAACUGUGGCUUCCUUGCACCACUCUCACAGGGUCUGUGUGAGGAUUAAAGGAAAAAACCCAUGCAAAGUGUUUGGUUGGUGCCUGGCACGGAGUAAAGGCUCAAGAGCUGUGGUGCCAGAGAGCAGCUUCAGGGGGCUUAGCCCAGCAGCAUCUCAGAGCAAUCCCCUAUCAACAAACAAAAAGGAUGUUCCGGCUCUGCAAACACGGUUACUAGACGAUCUUCGAAUGCCUCUUCUUGCAUGGAAUGACUGCUCUCGGCUUCUGCUCUUUGCAACCUGGAGGUGCCAUUGGGAUGCCCUGGCAGCCUCGCAUCUUACUUUAAUUAUUAUUUUAUUUUAUUUUUAUUUAUUGUUGUUUUAUUGUUUAUUAUUGUUGGCAAGACGCCGUUUGCAUAGUAAACUGAGACUGCUGCAUGACUUUUAUUUUAUUGGCUGCAUGACCUUAGCAUACUAAAGAUGAGUACAUUGUUAUUAUUGUUAUGGUUCUGAUUAGCUCCGUGACCGUAGCACACCGAAGCUGAGAGAGUGCGACCGUAGGGGGUUAAGGGCUCAUAUUCCAGAGCCAGUCUGCAUGGGUUUUAAAUUCCUCUUCCUCCACUUCCUCCACUUCCUAGUGGGUGACCUUGGGUCACCCGCUGAGAGUCCCUGUGCCUCAGUUUCCCUGUCUCUAAACUGGGCAUAAUAGUGUCUACCUCACUGGGUUGCAGGGAGGAUUAAAUGAGUAAUACGUAUGAAGUGCUUAGAACUGGGCCCGAUGCACGGAGGGAGUGUGCUGUUAGCCAUCAUUGUAGUCAUCCACUCAUUCCACCUGCAGGUUUUGAUUGUUGGCCUCCUCUGUGUCUGGUUCUCCCCGAAACAGUGGAUAUAUGCGUCUCCUGGGACUGCUAUAAGGGUGACAUGCCUGUUCCUUCCCCCAUCCCCUCUCUGUGUGCCCCUUCUCCUUGGUGGCACUCCUGGGCAGUCAUCAGCUUCCUUGCUUUACCGCAGCACCAGGGAGGCUCCUGUGACUUUCAGGAGAGCCUUGGGAGGGCACAGAACCUCUGUACUCCUCUUCGGGAACUCUCCCCACAGCUCCUGGCUCUUCGCUGUUCUGCAGGCCCAGUGUGAUCUGGAAGACGGGGAGAGAAUAAUCUCUGGCAGAGCGAUGUAGUUGCCACUGUAGAAUCAGAUGUGAGCCACUGUCAUUGAUGCUGGACUUUGCUUCCUGUCUCUGGCAGGCACUGGAAGAGAUGGCCUUUCAGACCUUCCUGUGAGUUUCAUUCAUGCUUCAUUCUUUCAUUCAUUUUUUUUUUCAUUCAGUCUCUUCCCAUUCUUUCUGCUUUCAUUCAUUCUAUUCGUUCAUUCUUUUGUUAUUCAUUCAUUUUUCAGUUUGAUUGUCUGCUUUGUCCUGGCCAUACUCUCAGGCACAGGAGAUGCACCCAUGAAGGCCCAGCUGGUCCAAGGCCUUGGGGAGCUCACAUCCCUAGCUGGUGGCAUGAGGAAAGGCGGGCAAGGAGGGGUACGAUGUGCCCAUACAGAUGCUGAUGGUGCACUCAGAGGCUGACUUGAGGGGUGAGGGAGGGCUUUCUGGAGGAGGUGACUUCUAUGUGCACAGGAGAGGAGGAGCUGGAGUUGGUGGGUGAAGAGGGGAGGUAGUGCUUGUUCCCCACAGAGGGGGACUUUACUUGCAGAGGCUCCAGGCCCUGAGGAAAGGAGUACCACAAUACACUGGUACUUUUUUCUCCUCGGUAGUCAGAGCGUAUUAUUCAGGUACAUCACUUGGGUGCAGGGGCUUGGGUGAGAGACCAGCAGGAGAGGUCUCCUUUGUGAGUCCCUCUUUCCAAAAGUGCCGCUGUACCCGGAGGUCUGGAAGACUUUACAAGUGUGUGACUUUCAGAGUGCAGGAACCCAGCACACCCUGUCACCAAACAGACCCACGAGGCCACCAUUCUCCCAGGACCCAGCUGUGGGAUGGCCUUGGCUCCUGCUUCUGGUUUUAUGGAGCCCCCCUCCCUUCUCUGUGAAACGGCACUGCCCAGGCUCGUUCAGGGAGGGGGAGAGAGCUGAUGUGCGAUGUGUGCGUAGUGCCCAGCGAAGGGCCCUUCACGCUGGGAGCUUUUGGCAAAUGCCAACUCUGGCAGGAGGAGGCACAGGGGAAGGAGAGUCUCGGGAACUUCCCCAGCUCUCCAGUGCUAGGAAUUUGACCUUUUCUAGGGGUUCAGAAUCCAGUGAUGUCCUGAAAUCUGCAGUUUCUGCUGCAGAAAGACAGUUUUUUAUGUGUUUCCGGCCACCGGGAUUCUUGAUAUCUUCUCAGUACCAGCCUUUGGACUGGUGCUCUUUGGGUCCCUGGGGAGUGAGAGGGGAAGUGAGAGAGGGCAAGAGACCUGUGGACACGCCUGCACGCCUGUGCCAGAGGCCUGUAGUGUCCCAAGGAGCCUGACAUCCCUCAGGGGCUGUAAGAGGUUAGGUGUAGCUAAAGGUUCCUGUUCCUCUCUGACAGAGUCAUCACUACCAGUUAGUAGUUAAUUCAUUGGUUUUCUGUGCUCCUACUGUGUGCAAGGAAUAUAGCAUCACAGUGAAUGAUGUUUCUGUUCUCGUGGUCAGGAGAGCCCAGUGCAGAGGCCUGAUGCUAUUGUAACAAACCAGCAUACAAAUGCUUAGCAUGGAUCGGGCGUGGUGGCUCAUGCCUGUAAUCCCAGCACUUUGAGAGGCCAAGUUGGGCAAAUUGCUUGAGCUCAGGAGUUCGAGACCAGCCUGGCCAACAUGGUGAAAGCCUGUCUCCACUAAAAAUACAAAAAUUAGCUGAGUGUGGCGGUGUGUGCCUGGAAUCCCAGCUACUCGGGCGGCUGAGGCAGGAGAAUUGCUUGAACCCGAGAGGUGGAGGUUGCAGUGAGCCGGGAUUACGCCAUCGCACUCUAGCCUGGGCGACAGAGGGAGACUGUCUCAAAAACGAAAAACCAAAUGCCUAGCAUGGCGGGGGAAUAAGGGCCCUGAAGAAGACAAGACCCACACAGGGCAAAGGGAGCAGGUGUUUGUGGCGUGGCCAGUCCUCUACCAGGCUAACACUUGAUGUGAAACUUUAAGGAGGGUGAAGGAGGGAGCCACCCUGGGGUGUCUGGGUAGAACAUUCCAGACAAGGAGAGCAAAUGCACAGGCCCCAAGGAGGACACGGAGGCAUAGGGAGCACUUGAGAUGGGGCAGGCAUCGAACUGGGUGCAGAAUACACACUUUCUCCUUUUAUCUAGUGAUCCUAAGAGUUUCCCCUGUGUAAUGCCAGUUUUUCUCCUGGCUGUGUGGAGGCUCCAAGGGGUCCAGCCUGCACACAGUGGAGGGGUCGAGAUUUGAACUGGUGACUGCUUGACUGCAUAGCCUUGGCUCUCGUUGGGCUGCGCGGGCUGAGCUGAGAGACUGGGGUAGGGGUUUUGUGGUGGGUUCCUGUUCCUGACCCAUGUGGGGUCUGGCCAUUACCCUUGCAGGCAUUAUCCUCGUGAGGGCUCAGGAACGGUGUCACCCAUCACAGGGCGACAGCUCCAGAGAUGUCUAGGGGGCUGGAGUGCCGGUGUCUGGGGUUGGCCUUACAAGAGCCUGGUGAGGACAGGGCUGGGCCAGCCCUUGCCUUUUGAGUCCCGUCUCUGUCACCGCAUGGCUGUGUGAGACUCUGGGCAAGUCACACCCUUUCUGAGUCCUCGUUUUCUUGGUAAAAACGGGGUUAGUAAAACUCCCUGCCCUGCUUCCUUACAGAGCUUUUGUGAGGCUCAGGGAAGAUUAUGUGUGGGAAAGCCCUCUGUGGGCUCCAAAGCCCUGGACACGAGAAUUCUGAUUUUCCUUUAUUUAAUUGCAAAAACAGUAUCAGUGGAACAUGGAAGAUAAUUUAAAAGAAGACGAAAAAAACCUCUUCAUACAAUUCACCCAAGUAUGGAAAUCCUACCCUACCCAAGUAUACACCAGCUGAAUGGGUUUGGAUGUAUUUUCAGAUAAAUUCCUCACUUGGCGAACUCUUGCCGCUUGACGUCCCCAACUCCACAAUCACGUGGAUCUGGAUCAUUUGGCACCCUUCCCUGUCUGAACUCGGGAGCUGGAUGGAUUUGGCUACUGAGGAUUGCUUGUAUCGAUUUUCCACUUAUUCCUCUUGGUCUUGGCCCAUCUGUACACAUACUUUUAUGUCAUUACAGGCACAGUGAACAUGCUGGUUUCUUUCCAUUUUCUCCUCUACCGUCAUCAGCGGAGAUGACGUUUUACCUAGUCUUCGCCGUGAUGGAAGCUUUUUAGUGGCCACGUGGUCAUCUUUUGUGUCACACCAUUUUUCAUGAAACCAUCUCCCUUUGGUUAGAUACUAAGGCCGUUUCCUGCUUUUCUUCCUCAAUAGAGUGUGCCACAGUGAAUAUCUGCGUGCCUGUAGCGUUUUUAUCCUUUCCUUUUGAUGAUGAAAGAUCAUUUGGAAAAAUUCCCAGGAGGGAGAUUAGUCGGCCACAGGGGUAUGAACAUUUUGAUGGCUUUGGAUAUCGAUGAGGCUCUCUUGCUUUCCCGCAGAGUGGAGCCCAUCUGUAAUGCCAUCCACAGGGUGCAAGCGUCCUUAUUUUAACACUGCCAUGUCCUCUCCGGGUGUCAUUGUUUUUCAUUUUUUUCUUAAAUUAACUUCACGUGUUGAAAAUGGUGCAGUGUUCAGUGUUAUUAGUCAACAGCUGGCUUUGAGACACAUGCCUGAGUGCCUUCAGCUCCUGGCUGAGUCCUCUGUCCCUCUGUCCGUGGCCACUCAGCCAUGAGCACUUCUGUUAGCGAUGAAGAUGAAAAAGUGUCCCUUCUGCCCAGGCUCUCCCUUCCUCCUCUGGCUGCAGAGCAGGGAGGGGUUUCAGUGGCAUCGCGGUGGCCGGGAGCGAGUGUGCUGGCCGGCUGGGCCUUGCUAGCAGGGCCGGGCCUUGCUGGCCAGGCCAGGCUAUGCAGGCCCUCGAGAGGGCCUGGGGACAAAGGCGCCUUGGGAGGAGGAGGCAAAACAGGGGAGGGAAGGGAGGGCCCUGGAGAAAAAGGGGGGAAGAGAAACAAAGACAAAGGCUGGCAAAAAUAGACCACGGAAACGGCAGGCAGCCGGGAUAAGGAGGACAAGAGGCAGGAUGUGGAAGAGGAGGGGAGGCGGAAGUUGUCGUGGGGGGUCGGGGAGAAAUGGGGAGUAAAGGGAGAGUGGGUUACGGGGAGCUGUGUGGGGUGGGGGUACGUGGGAGAGAGAGACCCAGAAAGACAGACACACAGAGAGAAGGGAGCGGCCGAAGAGGAGGGCCCGUGAGCGAGAAGAUGCAGAUGCCCCUUUAGUAGGAGGGCAUUGCUCCCUGCGCCCCUGGAAGGGACUCUGGGCUGGAAAGGACCAGAAUGCAGGGAGGAGCCGCUGGCGGGGGUCACUGGAAGCUUGAUUCGGGGGAAGCUGUAGGUUGGAGCUGGGAGACCCGAGUUCCUGCCCCUCCAGGGUCUUGUACGUCCUCACAGAGGACCUAGGGCCUUGAUCCUGGUCCCGGCACACAGACACUUCAGGGGUGAUGGAGCCACCACACCGAAUUCUCCUCUAGGGCCCUCCCCCAGCAUCAGAGUGCAGUCUGAGGGCAGCAGUGGGAGCUGGACUGGGGCCAUCUGUGCAAGGGGUUAUUGUGCCCAGGUGCACAGGCCGGAGCUCUGGGGUCACUCACCCUCCGCGUUACCUGUCGUUACCUGUCGUUACCUGUCGUUACCUGUUGUCUGGACCAUAAAAUGCAGAUGGGAAUGUCGCCCACUUCCUCAAGUCUUUGUGAGGAUUAAACGAAGUACGAAAUAUAAAGCACUUGGAGUGGGGCACAUAGUGUGUACCGUGUGACUCAAGGGGCUGUCCUCUUUAUGGUGACGAUGACAAGGGCAUCAGGACAGCAGCCAGCAUGGCGCAAGCCACCCGGGCCCAGCCUUGUUGAAUCUUCCGGCAGUGUGGCGAGUUAGGUCUGCUCGUUCCCACUCUCCGCAUGGGAAAACUGAGCUUCACAGUUAAUAUAAACACCAACAGUAAUAACAAUGGCAGCAACAAACUGCCGAAUAUGAGGGCCUAACAUACACGAAGCAACACGCACGUCGCAGAACCCACAGCUGAGGAGACCAGAGCUCAAAGGGGCGAGUCACCUGCUGGCUCACACAGCAGCCGGGACCGGGAUUGCAGGUGACCCACGUGGCUUCAGGGCCCAGGCCUGCCCUGUGACUCACGCGGCCUGUCACCCGCCGUUUCAUGUUUCAGGCCUCGCCUGUACACUGGUGCUUCUCAGGAAGUCUUAGGGAAGAUGACUUAUUUAUUAGCCGUUUUUUUAAAAUCUCUUAAUUAAAAAAACAACCAGUGUGAGUAUGUGGAAAUGUGAUUCACCAUGUGAUCGGGGAGGUCAGAGCCAGAGUCCCUGGCUCAAAGGUAACACCCCUGUCCACCUGGAUGAAGAAUGUUCCAGAAGCUUCCCUCCAGGCACGGUCCUUGCCUGCUGAGCAGUCACCGGGGGAAUCGGGGGCAGUUACCGGGGCCUCAGACUGUGGGAGCUGCCUCUUCCUGGGUCUCCAGCCGUGAUUUCAGACUCGUCUUUCAUCCUUCCCCUCUCGGUUGCCAGCCCAGUGCUGGAGGGACGCAGGGCAGAGCCCAGCCAGCUGCAGGUGUUUCCAGGCAUGUGCUGGGAAUGGAGCAGAUGCGGGGCUGAAGCUUUCCCCAGAACUGGCCUUUAUUGACGCAGAGGGUGGGAAAGAAGGCACGUGGCUGUGCUGGGAGAGGGUGGGUCUCCCUAUAGCCUGGACCUGGGAAGGGCCUUCUCUAGAGCUCUCCAGGGACGGCCAGACAGCUCCCCUUCCACCUUGGGGUGUAAGCGGAACAGGACACACUCCCCUCAGGAAGCACGGUAUCAAAGAGGGUCAGGAGGAGCCCCAGCCGGCUCCCGUUCUGAGGAGGCACCUGUGGGCAUGGGGGACCCCCGGGGCCGCCCCCCGAUGCCUCCGCUGAUGCUUAAGGUCACACAGCAGGACAUGGUAGCUGGGUUCAAACUCAGGUCAGGCCAACUGCAAAGCCUGUGCUCUUUCGACUCCUGGAUGGACACUGCCCAGGUGCCCCUGGGUAACUGAUACCCUUGUCCCCAAACAACUCUGAAUCUCUUUUCAUCAUGAAUAUUAUUAAUAACAAUAAAUACUAAUAACUGCCAUUUAUCAAGAGCCCCUACUUGCCAGGUGCUUUCUCAUUCAGCCUGCCAAGGAAGCCCGUGAGUUGGGCACCAGUAUCGCACUUUACAGAUGAAGUCAUUGAGGUACAGAGCAGCUAUGUAACUAGCCAUGGAUCAUAGAGCUAGUGUCGGAGAUGGCACCCACACACAAUUCUGAUGACAAAACCUUACACUUGGGGACUGUAAGGCUUUGGGCACAUUAGGUGACCUCUCUGAGCUUCAGUUUUGUCUUCUGUAAAAUGGACCUCAUAUGCUGUCCGUGGCAUAGGUUUGCAUAUGUGAAUUAAUGACUGUGGAGUACCUGGCACUCAGUGUUAGCUCUCACCAUCAUCAUCAUCAUUACUGUAGCAUAGGGUUUCUCAGUGAAACAGACACUGAUGGUCAGAGUGGACCUCUCAGCCUGGGGGAAGCAGAGGAUGAACCCUCUGGGGCGGGGCCCUGGGCAGGCUGGUUCAGUGAUAAGCAGGAGCCAGGCGACCCACAGGCUUCUUGGAUGGGCUGGGCGUGCAUGGCAUAACCGUUUGAGAACAACAAACCAAGCCGGCCGGGCUGCCGCUCUGUUUCCUGCGAGGAGGGAAGUUACAGAUCUCCGCCCUGGCGUCCGGGGAAGGAUGGGACAGGCUGCUGAGCCAACUGGGUACAUGGAAAACUCAGUCUCCUACAGCGCAAUUGAAGACGUUCAGCUGCUGUCCUGGGAGAAUGCCCCGAAGUACUGUUUACAGCUCACGAUUCCUGGGGGAACUGUCUUACUGCAGGCUGCCAAUAGCUACCUGCGAGACCAGUGGUUCCAUUCUCUGCAAUGGAAGAAAAAGAUUUACAAAUAUAAGAAAGUGCUGAGUAACCCAAGCCGCUGGGAAGUUGUCUUGAAAGAGAUCCGGACCCUGGUGGACAUGGCCCUGACAUCCCCCCUGCAGGAUGACUCCAUCAACCAGGCCCCACUGGAAAUCGUCUCGAAACUGCUCUCAGAGAACACAAACUUGACCACCCAGGAGCAUGAAAACAUCAUUGUGGCAAUCGCUCCUUUGCUGGAAAACAACCACCCACCACCAGAUCUCUGUGAAUUCUUUUGCAAGCACUGCAGAGAGCGGCCCCGGUCCAUGGUGGUCAUCGAGGUGUUCACCCCCGUGGUGCAGCGAAUCCUCAAGCAUAACAUGGACUUUGGGAAGUGCCCGCGACUGAGGCUGUUUACUCAGGAGUACAUCCUUGCCUUGAACGAGCUCAACGCGGGGAUGGAAGUGGUGAAGAAGUUCAUUCAGAGCAUGCACGGCCCCACAGGGCACUGCCCCCACCCCCGGGUCCUGCCCAACCUGGUGGCCGUGUGCCUGGCUGCCAUCUACUCCUGCUAUGAAGAGUUCAUCAACAGCCGCGACAAUUCCCCAAGCCUGAAGGAAAUCCGGAACGGCUGCCAGCAGCCGUGCGACCGGAAGCCCACUUUACCUCUGCGCCUUCUGCACCCCAGCCCGGACCUGGUGUCUCAGGAAGCCACGCUGUCUGAGGCCCGGCUCAAGUCGGUGGUCGUGGCCUCCAGUGAGAUCCACGUGGAGGUGGAACGCACCAGCACUGCCAAGCCGGCGCUGACGGCCAGCGCAGGCAACGACAGCGAGCCCAACCUCAUCGACUGCCUCAUGGUCAGCCCCGCCUGCAGCACCAUGAGCAUCGAGCUGGGCCCCCAGGCCGACCGCACGCUCGGCUGCUACGUGGAAAUCCUCAAGCUGCUGUCAGACUAUGAUGACUGGAGACCGUCUCUGGCCAGUUUGCUUCAACCCAUUCCAUUCCCCAAAGAAGCUCUCGCACAUGAGAAGUUCACCAAGGAACUGAAGUACGUGAUUCAGAGGUUCGCCGAAGACCCCAGGCAAGAGGUCCACUCAUGCCUGCUGAGCGUGCGGGCCGGCAAAGAUGGCUGGUUCCAGCUCUACAGCCCCGGAGGGGUGGCCUGCGACGAUGACGGGGAGCUGUUCGCCAGCAUGGUGCACAUCCUCAUGGGCUCCUGUUACAAGACCAAAAAAUUCCUGCUCUCCCUGGCAGAAAACAAGCUGGGUCCCUGCAUGCUCCUGGCACUGAGGGGGAACCAGACCAUGGUGGAGAUCCUGUGCUUGAUGCUGGAAUACAACAUCAUCGACAACAACGACACCCAACUGCAGAUCAUCUCAACCCUGGAGAGCACAGACGUGGGGAAGCGCAUGUACGAGCAGCUGUGUGACCGGCAGCGGGAGCUGAAGGAGCUGCAAAGGAAAGGCGGGCCCACCAGGCUAACACUGCCCUCCAAGUCCACAGACGCUGACUUGGCUCGUUUGCUGAGCUCCGGCUCCUUCGGAAACCUGGAGAACCUCAGUUUGGCCUUCACCAAUGUAACCAGUGCCUGCGCCGAGCACCUCAUCAAACUGCCUUCGCUCAAGCAGCUGAACCUGUGGUCCACUCAGUUUGGAGACGCUGGCCUUCGGCUCCUGUCGGAACACCUCACCAUGCUCCAGGUGCUGAACCUGUGCGAGACCCCGGUCACAGACGCUGGCCUGCUGGCCCUGAGCUCCAUGAAGAGUCUCUGCAGUUUAAACAUGAACAGCACCAAGCUCUCAGCUGACACCUACGAAGAUCUGAAGGCCAAGCUUCCCAAUUUGAAGGAAGUGGACGUCCGCUACACCGAAGCCUGGUGAAGCUCCCAGCUCAAGGCAGGAAGACGUUUGCAACCGCGACAAAAUAACUCUUGACUAACAGCCGCAGAGCAGCCGGUCCUGGGGUCCCACCCUGGUGCCCUGGCUGUGAGAUAGAUGGGGAGUCUUUCUGGGGGCGGAGGGGGGAGGGGGUGGGGAGGGGGCCCACAAGCACGCCCAGCCCCCGCCGAAUUCUUUUAGCUUCGUAAUUGGAACCUUUGACCUGAUCUAAAGUGGACUUUGUAGCAACAAGAGGAGCAUCAGCGGGUCGGGGAGGGGUUUGGGGGUGGGCUGGGGGGUGGGGGACCCUUUGUGGAUUUUCUUUGCCUUUGUGUUUGAUGCCGUCGUGUGGGAAAAGUCAACUCCGAUGCCACCAUUGCGGGCCGGACGAAGGAUGCUUUCUUCCUAGAGGCUCCGAGCUGAGCUGCGAACUCGCCCCCCGCCCUUGGGACAAGAAGACCCAGUCACAUCACUGCACCCGUCCUGUGUCCUCACCAUUGCUAUGCAAAGUGAUUCUUGUUGUACAUAAGAUUUAAAUAAUGCACCUAUUUAAGACAUGUUGACAAAUUGCGGGUCUGGGACCCGCCUCUUAUUUAUGAAGUCUUUGACCGUCCCCCCCGCCCGACCCCACCGCCCUCCCGCCCCCACCUGGCGUGUAGUACUGUAUAAACCAGUCAGCUGUCGGGUUAGUGGUAGUAUUAUUGUUAUUUUUUUAAAGGAAACAAACAGACAACAAAAAGAAGAAAAAAAAAAAGAACCUCCUUGGAAAAAUUAAUUGCUUUUUCGUAAUGGAUUCUCUAUGCUAAUGCUCUCUCGUCUGUCUGUCUGUCUGCCCACUCCCCCACCCACCACUGUGCGUUUCUGAUUUCCAAAUGUCUCCAACUCCCUCACGAGGUGGGGCUCAGGCUGGAGGAGGAGGGAUUAAGAUCCCCUUGCUCCACUAAGGCCCAAGCUCUUUCUCUCGGCACCUUUUAGACUUGAAUGGGAGGCUGCUAACCCGCCCUCUCCAGUCCACCCCGGUAAAAGAGCUGUUCCCCACCCCCAGGGAGCUCCUGUCCCUGUCAGCCUUUGCUGUCCCCUGUCCCCAACGGAGACUCUGUCACCCCUGGGCUCCCCCUGCCAUCGUGUGCUUCACGUGGCCCCAUGCAUGCCCGCCUCUCUGCAUGGUCUCUUGGGAAAAGAGAGAUGUGUCGCCUCCGCCAGUCCGACUGCCCUCCCCACCCCACCCCCGCCACCCCCCACAUGUGACCACUGCAACGAAGACACUCCUUCUGUCCCCACCUGCUCCGAAGACAAACCAACCUCCGUUUCUUUUAUAAACAGUCGGCUUUUUCUUAAUAAGCCCUCACUGUACAGAACAGCCCGUUGAUGGUUUAUUUGGGGUCCCCCUCUCCCCCCAGCCCUUUUUUCUGUUGGUUUAGCACAAAUACUUCCCUCCUCCGGCACCUCCAAACCUACCCCACAGUCAGUGUACUUGUUUUAUAUAUAUUUAAUCUUAUUCAAUGGAAACCAUGCUUUUGUCGUUUUAUACUUUGCUAGGUAGACUUUAUUACCCCCCCACUAUGCCCUCAUUUUUUUAAAAAAGGAAAAAAAAAAGAAACUGGGUUCCAGUCUUAAUUCAUUUUCCGUGCCAGGUUUUAUUUCGUGUGUGUGUGAGUGUGUUCUGUUUUGUGUUUUGUUUUUUGUUGUUGUUUUUAGUUGUUUGGUUUUCUUUUCUUUCCCCCCUCCGGUCCCAUACUUCACAGCACUCUGGUGCGGGAAGAAGCAGAAGCAAAAAAAAUAAAAAUAAAAAAAUAAAUAAAAAUAAAAAAAAUAAAAAAGGAAAAAAAAAAAAGAAGAAACAAGACAUGCCACCUUUCCCCUCGCACUGUUGCUUUUCCUGAUGGUUAAUACUACUGUCACGUAGCUGUGUACAAAGAGAUGUGAAAUACUUUCAGGCAAAAAUAAACUGUAAGUGACUCAUCAA